CUCUCUCUUCCAGCCGCAGCCGCGUUGCGGGGUGGGCGGCGGGUGGGGCAGGGGGCCUGGGCCCCGGCUGGGGCCUGGCGGACGCCGAGGGCUGGGUCCUUCCCUCCCCCGCGGCGCUUCUCAGCUGCUGCUGCCCCUCAGCUGGGAAGCAGCGGCUUCGCGUCUCCCGCCCCUCCCCCAGGCGGGGCACCGGGGAACCAGACGUGGAUCCCGGGGGCGCCUAGUCCGAGGGCAGCGACCGUCUCCUUCCCUCCAUGACCUGUCCCUUGGCCUGGGCUAGCCCCCGACCCCGGCACUCUGCGGCUUCUUCCCUUUAAGCUUGGGGGCGCUUUUCUGCCGGCAGGGCGGGCUGUACCUCACGCCUUGGAGUGGCCCUUUGGGGAGAGGAGGCCCAUGCGAGGGUGCUUGCGUUCCCGCCCAUCCUGUGUCUGUGUCCUUUGCUGGGAUUAGGGCAAAGGCAGCCGUUCCAUGCGGACGUGUUGCUGUCCUGUGUGUGUUGCAUCCUGCCCACGUGGUAGAGUGUCUCCCGCCCCCCCUCCCAGCUCCAUUUUUGCAGCUGGUGAGGAGGGAGGUUAACGGGAUGGUUUUUCCUCUGUGAUUUCCUCCGGGUGGCGUGGAAGGUGUUAGGGUCAGUUUGCUUUGCCGAGGCCGGCUGUUGGUUAGAUGAAGAAUCGAGAGUUGUACUCUGAAAUUGAGGCCAGUAGGGGACAUAACAGGGCUUAGUUUCAUUAACAUCUUUUUUCCUCUUCCAUUAGCUGCUCUUAUUCUUUUCUCUGUUGCUUAAUUAUAGAGAAUAAGCGCUUGCUACCGAUGCAUUCAGGUGUAUAGUUUUCAUUUCUCUGUUUUACUUUUUGUGUGUCUGGUUAGCAAAGGUUUUACUAUUCCGUGUUGGUGCAUUCCACGUCUGUGUUGUCCCUGGUUGGAUUCCUGAAUGAGUUAGAGCCAUUCACUCUAAUUCCUGAAGGAGUUAGAGAUUGGUGGGCACCUUUUUGGUCUUUUUCUGAGAUUUAUUUGUGUGUGUUUUCUUCCUUCUAUUUUGUUUCCCAGUGAAAAAGCGUGAUGUCAUAGGAGCGUUAUAUGCAUAGCUCUUUUUCUCACAAGGCAGCACUAGUUUCACCUAGUCACUUAUUUUGUAGAAGCUCUUUUACUUCACUUUUCCUCUUACUCUGUUGAGUACCCAUUGCACACUCUUUUUUUGAAACUGGUUUGAAACAUGGUUUGAGUAGUUUUUUUCUUAAUGUCUCUUCCAGAUUAGGGUUUCCAUCUUCUGUUUUGCUGUUUUGAGACCACAGAUUGUUCCCGCAAUAACAGUGAGAGAAGCCUAUUCCUCCUGGUCCCUAGCAAAUAUUUAUAGAAAAGCAGUAACUCCUCUCUUUUUCUGAGUGGUAUAUAUUAUAUAGACGUGAUUAAGUUUUUUAGUUUCUUAGAUAAAUAGGAGGAUUUCUCUUUUUGCUUUUGUGUCUCAGAAUUGAGGUGAAUCUUCUUGGUUUUGUGCUGCCGAGGACAAAACUGGGAAGUUUCUCAUGCUUUCAUUAGAUUUUUUUUGGAUGAGGCUAGAACGUGUUUAUUUUGGCUCUUUUUUGUUCAUUAGUUUGGGUAAAAUAAAAAAACUUAAUGUUUCAAAGUCACUUACUAGAUUCCAAAGUGGCCUGCAUUCUCACUUUUUCACAUUGUACAUUCUUUGAGUAUAUUUUUGACAUUUUUUUCCUUUUAUCUGGUACAGUUCGUAUAUUCCCUUUCCUUCUAUGUAGAAUGAAAAUAUUUAAAUAUAGAUUUUAGAUUAUAUUUUUUCAUUAUGCUAAGUAUGGGUGGGGCAGUGGAAAAUGGAGAAUGUUGUUCUGAUACAUACUGAGGCUUUUUGUUUUUUUUUGGUAAGUCAGCAUUUGUGUACUUCUGUAAAGUACCGAGUUAUCUAUGUGUGAAGUCUGUAUGAAGAGACGAAUAAGAUACGUGGUCUCUUGGAAAGCUUCAACUUAUAUCGAAAGAACAGAGUUUCUUUUUCUGUUCGGGAAACAUGUACAUCAUUCAGAAUUAUCAAACUGCAUCAAACUUCUCCUUGGGAUAACAGUACAACCAAGGUCAAAAGUGUAAGGGACAUUUGAGAAAGAUACAAAUUUCCAAAGGGAAAGAGGUGUAUUUCAGGAGAGUGAAGGGGCCUGUGCAAAGCGAGAGAAGUGGCAAUGUACAAAUGAUAUCAAGGAGCUUGACUGUCAGAUCAUCUGUGUUGGUGAAUAAUAAUAAAUGAGUUUAGGAUUGGUGAGGGGGUAUUGAUGGAGGAUCUUUCAAGGAUAGAGGGUUUAGUUUGAUAGGGUACCACAAUGGGUUCUAAAGAAUGAGAGUAAGAUGAUGCAUCUUGUUCCUGAGGAAGGUUUUUGUUUCAGCUGAGUGUCCUGGGAGUGGAGAGACUGAUUAGAGUGCUUAUGGAGAAUUUUAGGAAUAAGCUGAUGAGGGUCUGAUAUAAGAUAGUGGUUGUAGGAAUAAAAUAAUAGCUAACAUUUACUUACUGUAUGACAGGUAUUCUAAGCGCCUACGUUUGUUUAAUUCAUUAAAUCUUCAUAAUAAGGUAUUAAAAUCAGAAGGGACUUUGGGCAAGUUGCUUAACCUUAUGCAUGUAAUUAUUCCCAUAUACAAUGAACGGUUAGAUGAAAGGUAGAUUUUGCACUGACCAGGGAUAUAGAUGCUAGUAAAACACAUCAGUAGAUGUGUGUUGGGAGGGUAGUAGUAUAAUGAAGAAAGAGCUUUGAGGUUUGGAAUUUUGGGUCUUGAAAUAGGCUAAUAGCAUUCUGAGAAGAACCAGAAAGUGCAUCAUUUCCAGGAUAGGAAGAUUUUCUACAAGGGCAGGGUGUUGACAGUUUCAAAUGCGGUGUAGAAGUUCAGAAACAGUGACUACAAUGAAAAGACAAUUGAAUUAAAGCAGAAGAGAUAAUUUGUAAACUUAGAGAGAAAAUUGAAAGGAGGGGUAAGAAUAGAUGCCAGAUUUGUUUUUCACAGGAUUUGUAGAGACAUUAGUAUCUGAUAUGGUAAUUAUUAGUAUUUCCUUAAAAAAAGAAACAAACUUAUGUUCCAAAGCCAGUGAUUUUAUACUUUAACGCUUCUCUCCUUAAACUUUUAUUCUUUUUUUUUUUUAAAAAAGCUUUCUUGAAGUAUAAUUCACAUACCAUUUCAUUCACACAUUUAAAGUAUACAAGUCAGUGGUUUUUAGUGUAUUCACAGAGUUGUGCAACCAUCACCACAGUCAUUUUUAGGACAGCAUUUCAAAAAAAAGCCUUGUACCCAUUGGCAGUCACUCCCCGUACCCUCACCUCCAGGCAGCCACUAAUGUACUUACAAUCUUGUAGAGAUGUUGAUAAUUCCAAAUGCCUGUUGUGGGCAUUUCAUACAACAUACGGUCUUUUGUGUCUGACUUCUUUCACUUGCAUAUGUUUCAAGGCCCAUCCAUGUAGCAUGUAUCAGUAUUUCAUUCCUUUUUAUUGCCAAAUAAUAUUCCACUGUAUGUAUAUACUACGUUGAUAGCCAUUGCUUUAGUUGAUGGACAUUUGAGUUUCUUAUUCUUUCAUUAUUAUUAUUAUUAUUUGAGACAGAGUUUCUCUCUGUCGCCUAGGCUGGAGUGCAGUGGCGCCAUCUCGGCUCGCUGCAACCUCUGCCUCCCAGGUUCAAGCGAUUCUCCCACCUCACCCUCCACAGUAGCUGGGAUUACAGGCGUGCACCACCAUGCCCCGCUAAUUUCUGCGUUUUUAGUGGAGACGAGGUUUCACCAUGUUGGCCAGGCUGGUCUUUGAACUCCUGACCUCAAGUGGUCUGCCUGCCUCGGCCUCCCAAAGUGCUGAGACUACAGGUGUAAGCCACCGCGCCUGGUCAAGUUUCUUAAUUCUUUUAAACUCCUCCCCAUUUUCAUUGAAUCUUCACCCUGCCAACCCCUCACAUGGCCUUCUUUUAGAUUAUAACCUCUGCCAUGCAUUUUGCUAAGCAUUGGGGAUAUAAAGAUGAAUAAGACAUGGCCCUUGAACAUUCAUAUAGUGUUUUAUUGGUUUAUAUACAUUUUCUCAUACAUUCUCUAAUUUGAUCUCAACAACCCUGUGAUAAAGGCAGAAUAUCUUAAAGAUGAGCAAUUUGAAGUUUAGGUGACCUGCUUAGGGUUGUACACUUAAGUAAUUGGUGGAGCAGGUAGGUCUUCUUAGUUCAUAUUUGUGCUAUUUCCACUACUCUGUGCUGCUGUUUUAACUUAAAAAUUCUCAUGUAAUUUCCUGGAGACUUAGAGGGACUGGAAAAUGUACUGACUCAAAGAAUCACUGUUUUUUUUUGUUUGUUUGUUUUGUUUUUGAGACAGGGUCUCACUCUUGCCCAGGCUGGAGUGCAGUGGCACGAUCAUGGCUCAUUGCAACCUCAACCUCCUGGGCCCCAGUGAUCCUCCCACCUCAGCCCCCUAAGUAGCUGGGACUACAGGUGCGCGCCACCAUGCUCAGCUAAUUUUUGUAUUUUUUGUAGAGAAGUGGUUUCGCUAUGUUGCCCAGGCUGGUCGCUAACUCCCGGGCUCAAGUGAUCCGCCAACCCUGGCCUCCCAAAGCGCUAGGAUUACAGGCGUGAGCCACUGCAGUCAGCCCACUGAUUUUCUUCCGGACUUAAAAUGAAGAUUUUUUUCCCUAGAUUCUGCCACUUGUUUGUUCUGUGUUUUAGACAAAUCAUUUCAUAUUUCUUUUCUUUCAGAACUUUCAUGGAGUUCAUGUGAUGAUAAUGUAAUGAUAAUAAUAGCUAACAUUUUUUGAAGCCUUACUAUGGGCCUAAAAGUGUUCUAAGUACUCUACAUUCAUUAUCCAUAUCUUACAACCCUUAAUAUUUUAUAAAUUUUAUAAGUAGGUUUUAUAAAUAUAUCGUAGAUUUUAUAAGUUUAUUGUAGUUGUAAAUUUUAUAAAUACGGUAGUUUUACAGAUGAGGAAAUGGGCACAGAGAGGUUGAUUUGACUAAGGGAACAUAGCUAGGAAUGGAAAGAGCCAGGAUUUGAACCCUUGUAGUCUAUUUUCAGAACUCUGUGGCUCUUAAUCACUACACUGUUCUGUUUACUGUGUUACGAAUUAAUAGAGGAUAAUAUUUCAAGUAAGGGCAUGAUAGAAUAUGAAGAUUUGAUUUUGAAUGUAGUUGGGGAAACAGUUAAACAGCAAUUUUAACUUGACAUCGCAUCCGCAUUUCUUUUAAAAGUGGACUUAACACUACAGUGUACAAAGAUACAUAUUGUUUAGACAUUUUUUUGUUUGUCCCUGCUCAAAACUUCUCAGCUCAGAAAUUACAUUAUUUUCACUGAUCUUCACUGUUGGCUUUGUUAGUCACUUAGCUUUCCACAUUGCCACUAUUCAGAAACCUUGGCUUGAGACAGCUAAAGCUCACUUUUACCUCUCUCCUCAGCCUUCCUUUAACUGUGAAUUUUUGUUUUCCAUUUUGAACAGUUAGCCUUUCAGUCCUAGAGGGGGUUAUUCUUUACCUCUUCCACUCCAAAACCCAGAAAACACCACAGUGGCGUUUUAUAACAACUGUCACAAAAUUUGACCAUCUUAAUUGGCAUAACAUGAUUUUAGUGCACAAAUAAGAACCAAAGCAUAGUGUUUUGGUUAAAGAGAUUGACUUACUCUGAAAUUGGAAAAGGCAUCUGCUGUACAGGAUUUUUGAUUUAAUAGAAUUUGUUAUAACCAGAUCAGCAGAGCAUUAUUACUGUGGGCCAUCUGUUGGAAUAUGGAAAUAGCUUUGUUAUAUGGAACCAGAUGUUGUUUUUAUAUUUAUAACAAUGACAUUCUACUUAUUUUAAGUAACCUUUUGUAGUUAGGUACCUUUGGCUGCGAUUCUAUUUGACAUGUAUAUCAACUGAUAACCUGAGAAUGUGAUGUCUUUCAAAGUGGCUAUUAUUCUGUGGGAUCAGGACAACACAGAUGAAACAAAAAGGAAAUGAGACUCAUACAGUGUCAAACUUUAGUGCUAUAACAAGAUAAAAUAUAGGAAAAAUGACCUGGUGUGGUGGCUCACGCCUGUAAACCUAGCAUCUUGGGAGGCCGAGGCAGGCGGAUCACUUGAGGUCAGGAGUUUGAGACCAGCCUGGUCCACAUAGUGAAAUCUCGUCUCUACUAAAAAUACAAAAAUAAGCUGGGCAUGGUUGUGGGUUCCUGCAGUCCCAGCUAUUUGGGAAGCUGAGGCAGGAGAAUCGCUUGAACCUGGGAGGCCGAGGUUGCAAUGCCGCUGCAUUCUAGUCUGGGCAAGGGAGUAAGACAUUGUCUCAAAAAAAAAAAAAAAAAAAAAUAGGAUAAGUAUGAAUAUGUGAUAUGAGAUAAUUAGGACCAUAUUAAAUAAGAGCUCUGACCUUGAGACUAUUAAUAAAGGCCUCGUUUCUAAUAAUUACUAAGCCACUUGGUUGCUCUAAGAAUUUUUACCCUAAAUCUAAAGUGAUUUGAUUUUGAUGUAAUUGGACCUACAUUAAUACCACACUGUCUGACCAUUGUUUCCCAUCAUCAAUUGAUGAAAUAGUCUGUAACAAGACUCAUACUUGUAGAGUGGGACUCAAACUUAGAGUGCAAUAAGAGGAACUGUUUUUAGAACACAGACUUAGAGAACUCUGUUCUGAAUUGAACGCUAAUAAUUUGAAGAUGACUGGGUCUUUGGGUAGGAAUUUUUAUUUUUUUGAGACAAGAUCUUGCUGUGUCACCCAGGCUGGAGUAUAGUGACUCCAUGAGAGCUCAUUGCAACCUCCCAACUGCAGGGCUCAAGCGAUCCUCCUGCCUUAGCGCCACAAGUGGCUGGGACUAGAGGUGCGUACCACCACACCUGGCUAAUUUAUUUAUUUUUAAUUCAGACAAGAUCUGACUAUGCUGGCUCCCUAGGCUGGUCUUGAACUCUUGGCCUCUUCCUCCCUCCUUGGUCCCCCAAAGUGCUGGGAUUGCAGGCGUGAGCCACCAGGCCUGGCCUGGGUGGGAAUUUUUAGAGAGUCUCUCCAGAAACUGCAUGAUAUCUAUUUUUAUUGUCUUCAAAUCAAUGUAGAGUCUGUGGAUUCCAUAGAGUUGGCCAGCUAUUCUAGGAUGAGCUUUACCCAGUAAACUGACUUUCAGUCAGAGUUUUCACCUGGAGUAUAAAACAAAAAGUUCUAACGGAAUUCUCCUACCUAGAGUCCUCCUCAGUGGUAUAGUGUUUACUAAGGAAAUAAGAUUGAUCUUCUGAUUGAUUGGUAGAGUGUGGUGCCAGUGUGACCUUAUUAAAAACCUUGUAAAUUGGAAUCAUCUUUUUUUUUUAAGAUUGGGACCUGACCUUUGACACCACUAAUAAGCCUUGUUUCCAAUUAGCACUAUUGUGUUGAAACAGAUUUGUGAGAGGAAUGGAUAAUAAAGGAAAGACUGCUAGAACUUACUAACUGUUGCAAAUUUUGUUUGCUUACAGAGAGAGGGGAUUCAAUAUGAUGGAAGUAGGUUAUCAUAAAGACUCUAGAUUUUGGCUGGUGGUACAUGGGUGCUUAUUAAAUUAUUAAAAUUAACUUUAAAAAGUUUCUGUGGCUUGGCCAUCAAAUUUUGGGUAAUUACAGACACAACAGUCAAACAUGCAGCAAUCAGGGUCAGGUUGGCCUUUCUGAAUGAGGAUGGAGCAGACUGUUACGGCAGGAGGUGAAUGAUACAUGGCGUCUCUUUCUGCUAGGAUAGUUGGGUCUGUGAGUCUAUGACACCUUACUUGUCUACCCUGUGUACAGAACUGGUGAUGGUAUUGUCCCACUGUGUAUACGUGGGUAGCCGUCACCAUCAGAAAUGGCACCUUUGUGUAUCAGAGGAAGUCGUGUUUUAUAUUAUUGUAGGGGAUGUGUAUUUUCAAAAGAUUUCCACCUUACAUUUGAAUAAUAUUUUUUCAAAAGUGUUUUAUCUGAUCUGUUGGAUUUUGGAGACUUAUAACAGCCUUGUGAUAUGUGUUAAUAGUGAUAUGUGUUAAUAGUGAUAUUCCUAUUGGCAAAUGGAGAAGAUGAGAUAGAAGCUAGGUAGGACUCAGUGCCACUCAGUUAUUUAGUGGUGGAACAGAUGCUGGAACCCAGACCCUGCAUUCUCCUUGUUUCUUACUCUUAGUAUGAAACUGACAAAGUUUUGGUGAGGAACUUGCUCUGGAUUUUUGAGGUAAAAAUGGAAGGUUAUAGACCCCAAAGGACCUGGCCUACUUGGAGCAGAACAUAUGAUAAUAUCAGACUUAGAGUACAUAAAACCAAUGGGAGCGGUUUCUCCCCUUGUUAAAUUUAGGUCCAUUUCUAGUCAUUGGAAGCAUUUUUACUUGAAUCUGCAUUCUUUGUCUUCGUAGAAUUCAGGAGUUAAGGGAAACUUUAAAGGAUUACUCAAUAGCAGAUUUGGUCUUGUUUUAUGUAAGUAUACAUCUAUAAAAUUUAGACAUUGAAAAAGUAUCCCUGGAACAUGAUUCCACUAAGGAUGCCUAGGUUACUGCCACAGUGGGAGAUGUGUUGUCUGUUGCCUGGUGGUUGGGAAGAGUAACAGUAUAUAGAGAAGUUAUAUCUGCAUAGAAAAAAAAGACUGGGAGAGAAUGCAUCAUAAUGGUUCUUCCCUGUGGAACAGUAGAGACCUAGUCUGCCUUCUUUCACAAGAUAAUCCUUCAAUUAUUUGAAGGUGAUUAUUCAGCAUAUAUCUCUUGAGUACCUGUGCAUGCAAGACACUGUCCUGGAUAUUGUGAGAGAUCCAAAGAUUCUCUUUGUGGCCAGAUGGGUUUGUAUGGACAGGCUUGUCCAUCUGUAACUUCAUUAAGGAUGACAUCUGAACUGGAGAGCAGCCUAACGUCUAUGGACUGGUUACCACAGCUCACCAUGAGAGCAGCCAUCCAAAAAUCUGAUGCUACACAAAAUGCACAUGGAACAGGAAUUUCUAAGAAGAAUGCACUCCUUGACCCAAAUACAACUCUGGACCAGGAAGAAGUCCAACAGCACAAAGAUGGGAAACCUCCAUACAGUUAUGCCAGCCUCAUUACAUUUGCAAUUAAUAGCUCACCCAAAAAGAAAAUGACUUUAAGUGAAAUUUAUCAGUGGAUUUGUGAUAACUUCCCAUAUUAUAGAGAGGCUGGCAGUGGUUGGAAGAAUUCCAUACGACAUAAUCUGUCAUUGAACAAAUGUUUCCUUAAAGUGCCUCGAUCUAAGGAUGACCCUGGAAAGGGGUCCUACUGGGCAAUAGACACCAAUCCGAAGGAAGAUGUGCUGCCUACUCGGCCAAAGAAGAGGGCACGAUCUGUAGAACGGGCCUCAACUCCAUAUAGCAUAGAUUCAGAUUCUUUGGGAAUGGAGUGUAUUAUUUCGGGAAGUGCCUCUCCAACUCUGGCAAUCAACACUGUGACUAACAAAGUAACAUUGUAUAACACUGAUCAGGAUGGUAGUGAUAGCCCACGCAGUAGCCUUAACAACAGUCUCUCAGACCAGAGUUUGGCAUCUGUUAAUUUGAACAGUGUUGGAAGUGUGCAUAGUUAUACACCGGUGACAAGCCAUCCAGAAUCAGUCUCUCAAUCAUUAACUCCUCAGCAGCAACCACAGUACAACCUUCCAGAAAGAGACAAGCAACUACUUUUCUCAGAAUAUAAUUUUGAAGAUCUUAGUGCCUCAUUUCGGAGCCUUUAUAAGUCAGUUUUUGAGCAGUCACUUAGUCAACAAGGUUUGAUGAACAUCCCUUCUGAAUCUUCCCAGCAGUCCCACACUUCAUGUACCUAUCAGCACUCUCCCAGCAGUACAGUGAGCACUCACCCACACAGCAACCAAAGCAGCCUGUCCAACAGUCAUGGCAGUGGCCUCAACACCACAGGCAGUAAUUCGGUUGCACAGGUCUCACUGUCUCACCCCCAGAUGCACACACAGCCAUCUCCACAUCCUCCCCAUCGACCGCAUGGUUUACCGCAGCAUCCGCAGCGUUCCCCACACCCAGCACCACACCCACAGCAACACAGCCAGCUCCAGUCCCCUCACCCCCAGCAUCCCUCUCCACAUCAACACAUACAGCACCAUCCGAACCAUCAGCAUCAGACGUUAACACAUCAGGCACCCCCACCCCCACAACAGGUAUCCUGUAAUUCUGGUGUUUCAAAUGAUUGGUAUGCGACACUUGAUAUGCUAAAAGAAAGCUGUCGAAUUGCCAGCAGUGUUAAUUGGUCAGAUGUAGACCUUUCACAGUUUCAAGGUCUGAUGGAGAGUAUGAGACAGGCAGAUCUCAAGAACUGGUCUUUAGACCAGGUUCAGUUUGCCGAUCUUUGUUCUUCUCUUAAUCAGUUCUUUACACAAACUGGCCUUAUACAUUCACAGAGUAAUGUUCAACAAAAUGUUUGUCAUGGUGCCAUGCAUCCAACAAAACCUUCCCAACACAUUGGAACAGGAAAUUUGUACAUAGAUUCUAGGCAAAAUCUCCCUCCUUCAGUGAUGCCACCCCCUGGUUAUCCUCAUAUCCCACAGGCACUCAGCACUCCAGGAACAACGAUGGCAGGCCAUCACAGAGCCAUGAACCAGCAGCACAUGAUGCCUUCCCAAGCCUUCCAGAUGCGGCGUUCCCUGCCUCCAGAUGACAUCCAGGAUGACUUUGAUUGGGAUUCAAUUGUGUAGGGCUUGUUUCUGCAAGACACCAGACCCUAACGUUACCUUUCUGUGCAGUGAAGGGAAAGGUUUAAGAGAAUCCAGUUGAGAAAACAAACUUGCUAAUCACUUUACCAAUGUUAUCAAAAUUACUUUUGAAGACAAUCAGAAGGAUUUUAGCUGGAUAACUUACUGCUUUUAUCUGACCCAAGCAAGUACUACAUGUUUGUCUCCCUGCCAGCUGCCCUAUGUAGCUCCUAACUGUUGUGUGAUUUGGACGGCUUUUUGCAUAUUUGUGUCAGUUUGAUGUUAACCACAAGUGCCAGACUGAUUUUUCAGACGGAGCCUAUUUUGCUGCAAGCAGUUUAUAUAAAGAUACAUAUGUGUAAAUAUAUGUACAAAAAUUACUGAAAGGCUUCAGUUUUUUCUAAUUGGAUUAUUAUGUCUUGAAAGUUAUUGUCAGUUUUUAUUCCUUGUUAGGCUAUUUUCUGCAGGAUGCUUUUAACUGAUGUAGGAAACUGAAAGGAAAUAGAUUUUUUCCAAAACCCAGUUCCCCUUAUUUAAUCUUUUUUAGAAAUGUGGGUAAUGAAUUCUAUCUAAUAAGUCAAGGAAACCAGAAUUUGACACACUCCAACAAUCCGAAGGGGCAUGUUGCUCCUGAGCAGCAUGAAGAACUGACCAAAUUGGUUUUGAUGCUUGGGGGAUCAUAGAGUAUUUAUGUCUGCUUUUCUAAAUCUGCAUUAUAAUAGCUCUAAAAUUUGUUGAUUGGUAAGAAAUUGGGCAUUGCUUGGCUCUUUAAACACAUCAGUGCUUCCACAUUCACCUAUGUAUUUAUUAUUCAAAAGUGUCAUUUUAAUAUUUAUUGCUACCUUCUGUGAAUGCUUAGCUCCUGUCGGGUUCAUUAAGGAGAAAUGUGUCUGAAAGCACAGAACUAUUAUUAUUUUUUUCUUUUUUUGAGAUGGAGUCUUGCCCUGUUGCCCAGGCUGGAGUGCAGUGGCACGAUCUCGGCUCACUGCAACCUCCGCCUCCCGGGUUCAAGCAAUUCUCCUGCCUCAGCCUCCCGAGUAGCUGGGAGUGCAGGUGCACACCGCCAUGCCUGGCUGAUUUUUUGUAUUUUAGUAGAGAUGGGGUUUCACCAUGUUGCCUGGGCUGGUUGCAAACUCUUGAGCUCAGGCAGUCUGCCUGCCUCAGCCUCCUAGAGUGCUGGGAUUACAGACAUGAGCCACUGCGCCUGGCCCAGCGUUACUUUUCUUGAUAAGAAUUUACAGAUAAGACACUCAGAGAGACAUUGUGUCAUUCUCUAUCAUCACUCCUUUUACCAUGUGAAUAGAUUUCUCUGUCUUGGCAUUCUUGCUGAUUCAGACUUAUUAGUUAAAUCGGAUUUUUCUGGAAUUUGAAUCAGAUUUCAUUUGGGCAACAACAGCAGGGCAGGGUUUCUAAAGCAGGUUUCCCCACUCAUCUAGGUUGUCUUGAAAGGAGGAUAGAGCCACUUACAGUUUUAUUUGCUUCAGUGUUUAAUGUAGAUAUUAUGUGGCCUGCUGUUUCUGUUGUCUUGUAUGUCUGUGUAUGCAUGACAUUUGGUCCCUUUCUUUGAAAUGCAGCCCCUCUUACGGGUUUUUUAGUGGUGGUGGUUUGUUUUGUUUCAUAUCAUAUCACAGUUUGCAUGGACUGAUUAUCUUAGUUUUAUGAUAAAACUAGAAGAAAUGAGGGUUUUUUUUUAAUGAAUAGAUUUUGAAUUGAUUCUUUAGACCCCCCAAAAAGUGUCAGUUCUAAUGGGGAAAUAUAUUCCAUCAAGUCAAAGAGUAAUAACUGCUCACUAGUUGCUUUUUAGCAUCUCUGGUCUUAUCAGCCAUGCUAAAUCACUUUAAUUAGCCUUAGUGAUUCUAUGGUUGAGUAAUCUCUACUUGAACUAAACAAACAUCUUUUGUUUCUGUGUGUGUGUGCUGUGUGUGAGAGUGUGCGCGCGCGUGUGUGUGUGUGUGUUUUAAUGGAGUGUUGCCUUGAAUGAAUCACUGGGAAGCCAGCCAUGGUAAGGGCUGGUGAGGUUGGGGAGAAAGGAAGAGCUUUAUGUUUCUCUGUUGUUUGGACCCUACUUGGCAUGAAAAAGGAAGCUCAGUUCCAGCCCCUUGGAUCAACGAAAAUCAGAGGAUUCUGGAAAGGCAGCCAACUUGCGCCUCUUAGAAGGAUCAGAGGCAAGAUGAGAUGGCAGCCUGCAGAGUAAAUGCUUGAAAAAAGAGGGGUGAUUUUCAAUGGUUUGCUUAAGUCACUGUUUUCUAGACACCAAAAUAGCUGUUUUGAAACUGUUUUAAUUGCUUGGGUAGCAAUGUGCACUUUAAACAAUUUGGAUAUUGGAAUGCAGUCUCAUACUGAGUGAUUUGAGUAGAACCACUGAUGAUGAUUUUAUAAAUUGUGUGAAGCGAAUUUCCCAUUUGGCAAUCAUUUACUGAUUUGCAGUGAUGAAUAUUUUUAUGAGAAUUUAAACUUAGCAAGAAUGGCCAUGGAGGCAAAGCCUUCACCCAGACCCAUCCCACUCUCCUGUGAUCCAGGUGGUCCAGGAGCCCAGGACAGGCCUUUUCUGUGGGCCCUGGCCAGACAGGGUUACCUGGUGAGGUGCAGAGAGUCCCUCUAGUGGCCAUUUUGUAUGGUAGUUGCUAAUGCAGAACAAGUUCUGUCUUGGGCUUAAAUUGACUGAAGACUUUAGGGGGAAAGAAUAGUAAAUGCAUGUAAACAAAUGGGGACACUCUGUUCAGGAGAAUAAUCCGACUGGCAUUUGUGGCAGUUUUUGAAAUGUAAAUGUAUUCAUGUGUGUUCUUGUAAAUACGUGUCGCUCAGAUGUCCUUUGAAGUGGGAGGGAAUCAAUCCGGGGAUAAUUUCAAAUGGAAUAGAGUAUUUUGAUAUUGUUCAUUCAGAGGGUGAUGUGUACAUAUCUAUAUUGUAUAUAUGUGAUGAAAAUGCAUUGGCUUUUUGUGCAGAUACAACCUGCUCUCUGUACUGCUGUUGGACAGUCAGUGUUUUAAUGUUUCUACAGUUUUGCUAUUGCACGAUUUCAUAUUUUGCCUCUAUGAUGAACGGCAACCAUUAUUUGUAACUGUUUAGUGCUGUAAAGAAAUAUUCCAAGUGUCAUUAGGAUUGUUGCUGCCAGAACUGAUAUGCAUGAAUGGCACUUAAAAUAAAUAUAUUAUGUUAACUCUA